AAGGUCCGCCUCCUACCUCCUUCUGCUUCGGGGAGGGCAUGGGAUCAGCUACCUGUUUCUGCCUCAACCACGGACCAAUAAUAUGAGAUCUUUGUUCACCAGUUCUACAGUGAUGGGGUGCUUCCUUUUGGCUUCUGGAAUGGGUGCGUUUGCUUCUGAGGAUCUCCAGUGUCACAACAAACACAUGCCAGCCCUGUUUUACAGGGAGCCCUGGAGGAGUUGGGAUAGAGGCCACAUUGACUGAGGGUAGUUGCCAGGGUCCUGCAGUUAUACACAAAGUCCUUAGGAUAAGACCAUGGCCUUGAGAGCAUGUGGCUUGAUCAUCUUCCGAAGAUGCCUCAUUCCCAAAGUGGACAACAAUGCAAUUGAGUUUUUACUGCUGCAGGCAUCAGAUGGCAUUCAUCACUGGACUCCUCCCAAAGGCCAUGUGGAACCAGGAGAGGAUGACUUGGAAACAGCCCUGAGGGAGACCCAAGAGGAAGCAGGCAUAGAAGCAGGCCAGCUGACCAUUAUUGAGGGGUUCAAAAGGGAACUCAAUUAUGUGGCCAGGAACAAGCCUAAAACAGUCAUUUACUGGCUGGCGGAGGUGAAGGACUAUGACGUGGAGAUCCGCCUCUCCCAUGAGCACCAAGCCUACCGCUGGCUGGGGCUGGAGGAGGCCUGCCAGUUGGCUCAGUUCAAGGAGAUGAAGGCAGCGCUCCAAGAAGGACACCAGUUUCUUUGCUCCAUAGAGGCCUGAGCUGACUGGAGCAGAGUCAUUUGCUUCAGCAGGAUCCUUGUGGGCCUUCUAAGAUGAAGCCACCCUCAGGUCCAGGGAAGGUUGUGCUGGUAUUUGGCUCAUGACAGCCAAGAGCAGAUUUGUGAAAUCGGCUCAACUCCCAGGUGAGAGCAAGCAAAAAUCUUGGCUGGGUGGAAAGGAAGGCAAAAGAGUAAAAAUUAAAAAGGCCAGGCCCAGUAAGUGUACCUUGUACUUUAUAAAUAAACCUCAAGCAGCUCAA